GCAUGUCUCGCUCUCUUCCAUCCUCCCCCUUACUCACACAUCAGUCUAUCAGUGUUCGGCUCCAGCCUGUGAAGAAGUUAACUGGUAAGGACUUUACCUAAAUUUAGUAUGUUUAACAGGAAACCUAACGAUAUGACACUUUAGGUCACGUCAGAUGUGUAUAUUUGCAUCUUUAGGUUUUUCCUCUCUGGCCUUCCUAAUGUCACAGACUCUUGACACUAAAAAAAAAACUCCAACUGAUUUUAAUUUAGAGAAUUAGAACAGUACUCAGUUUGACAGAUUGAUGUAUUUAUUUUCUAAAUGACCCAUCUGUUGUGAACAUAUUUUUCUAGGUUUUCAGGAAGUUCCUGGUUUUGCCAGAAUACACUGUUGUUCUGAUUUCAUUUAUCAGCUUGUUCAUGUCAGGUUAACAGAUGGAGACAUUCUAAUUUUAGGAUAAUAGGAGCUUGAUAGUUCAGCAAAGGUACAUCAGUCGUAUUUUAUUUGAAAUUGCUAUUUGUAUAUUUUAUAUAUUUUUUUAAAAGAUAAUUUAGAUAUUUUCCUCUACACUGGACAUUAACUUCUUAGGAUAUUUACUAUAAUUCAUAAGUUAUGGAUUAUGUUGACUUUAAUAUGAUCUCACAAUAUGUAUUACCCAUUUAGAUCAAGUUGUUAGGUGUGAAACUGUGGCUUUAUUAAAUGAACUUUUGUCCUUUUACGUCUUUUCAGGAAAUAAAUUUUAAUAUAUAGUUGAAGAAUGCUUAUGUGUGAAAAUAUGUAAUCCUGGGUCACUUUGUUAGAUUUCUUCUAGCAUUAUCAAUAUAUCCCUGAUGUCAGUAAGUUGGCUAGUAUUGAUGGGUUCUAAGUGCAUGGAGGCAUGAAAUUAAGUUAUUCACAAAGGAUAUGUCGACUGUUUCCUGUCUGACAUUGAGCUAGACAGUAGAGAAGUUUGAUUAUCAUUAUGACAAUUCAGAAGAAAAUGAGAAAUGAAAUUUUUGGGCACUUCUGUCUAUGUAGAGUGAAACUUUUUCACUGUUUAUAAUUUUCAUUAAAAUAAUAGCAUUUCUUCUAUAGUUCUACAAAGCAUAAAUUAUGCCUCUUUACAUUGUGUAUUAUUGGCAUUUUCAAAAAAUAAAUGAAUCAAAGUCACUUUGGCCGUUAGAUACUUCAGUCUAAAGACACUUUGGUCAUUAGAUUAAAAAAAUAGGUAAAAUAGCCUAAAAACAUAAUAUCCUGAAAUACCAGUUCCCUUCUAAUGUCCAAAAAUAUGAUGAAUUUUAUGUGAUUAGGCUUAAAUAAAAUCUCAGUGCUUAGAAAUUCUCCCUGUUUUACAGUCAAAGGUAUUAUUGAUUACUAAAAAUAUAAAAAUCCCAAAUCUGUUGGCUGUCAUGUGAUGUGUUUCAUUUUACCACACAGAGUGGAAAAAAUAGUAAGUCCAGUUUCUAUGUAGAAGUGAGCUGGAUUGCCUGAAGUUUUAGAGAUACCGCUUUCCUAUCCCAUUUGCCUAUCUUAAUUUGAAUGUCAACUUAAUAGUCAACGUUUAUUAAGAGAUAACUAUUAAAUAUAACAAAGUCAAUAACAUACCUAAUAUCACAGAGGUAUUGUAGUGAAGCAGUAAUGCAGAGUGUAAUUGAUUAAUGACAUGUAUGAACUUUUGAGUUUUAAUUUUACAGUAUUUGAAGCUUCUGUAAUUUCUCAUAGUUUAAUUUACUGAAGACUAUCAAAGGCCUAGCAAUUUAAUGAUUAAGAAUGCAUUUUUAAAUUUUGGAAGAAAACAACUUUACUGAAAGAGUAUGUCAGGAAAAUGUUUCUUUGGUCAAUUUUCUGCCAAGUGAAGCAGAUGAUAAGAAUUGUCUAGUUUAACCUGGAAUGAAAUUACUUUGAAAUUCAAAAUAAAAACCUCAGUAGAUUAUUCAUCCAUUAUCCCUUCUUAACCUAAUCAUCAGUUACCCCUUCUUUUCUAAUUAUAUCUUGUUAUAAGUAAGUAAAAGGAAAGUUGAAUGGAAAAAAAUUAGCCGACCGUAAAGAAAUUUUCUCCAAAGAAUGGUUCUUUCUUGGCAUUAAUUAUCAAAAUGCAAUAAUUUAAUCAGGCCAUUAGGACUACACUUAGUAAUUUCUCCAUUUCCAUACAUUCAAACUUUCAAGUGCCUUGUAUGUAUUCAUAUUACCAACCAAACUGAAUGAAUAGGGCCAGAAGAGUCAUCAUAUUCUAUUUUCUUUGUGACUUUCUAAUAGUCUCUUGUCUCUGGCACAGUUAAAAGCAGUUUGCUUAUUAUUCUUCAGUGCUUUUUACUUAAUCAUUCAACAGAUAUUUGUCUAAGGCCCAUUACAUGCCUAGGCACUGCUCUAGAUAUGAUAGAGUGGUGAAAAGGACCACUAAGACCCCUGCCUUCAAGGAUUUUAUAUUUCAGUUGAGAGAAGAUGUAAUAAAUGCAUAGCCAGUAAAUAAAUACUUGAAUUUUAAAUGGUGGCAACUACUACAAAGGUAAUGCAAUAUGGAAGGGGAUAGAAACUGGGGUUGAGGUAGAGUUUCCUUCUAUGGAAUGACUGGGGAGAGUCAAAGGAGGAGAUAAUUGAGCUGAGUUUUCAAUUUAAGAAGGAGCCAGCCAUGGGAAGAUCUGGGAUCGGAGCUUUCCAGGCAGAGCUAACAGUCAGAACAAAAGUCCUAAAGCAGAAAUGAGCUUGGCAUGUUCAAGGAAUGGAAAGAAGGCAAGUGUGGCCUGAGCAGAGUAAGUCUGAAGGGACAGUAGUAGAAAAUGAGUUAGAGCUGGGGCACGAUGGCUCAUACCUGUCAUCUCAGCACUUUCAGAGGCCGAGGCAGGAAGAUUGCAUGAGGCCAGAAGUUUGAGACCACCCUGGACAACAUAAUGAGACCUUGUCUCUACAACAAAUAAUUUAAACAAAAUAGCUGGGUGUCAUGGCAUGCCACCCAUAUGUAGUCCUAGCUACCAAGGAGGCUACGGUGGGAGUGUUGCUUGAGCCCAGGAGGUGGAGCUGCAAUGAGCUCUGAUCGCACCACUGCACUCAGGCCUGGGAAACAGAACAAGCAAGACCCUGCCACUAAAAAAAAUAAAAAUAAAUAAAUAAAUAAAAAGAGUUGGAGAGGUGGGCAGAAGCCACAGUUUUUAGGGUCACGGUAAGGAGCCUACUCUGAUUGCAGGAUUUUUUUUUUUUUACCUUAUUUAUUCUCUCUCUAUUGUUUUUUCCUUUUUAUUUUUAUUUAUUUAUUUUUAUUAUACUUUAAGUUUUAGGAUACAUGUGCACAAUGUGCAGGUUUGUUACAUAUGUAUACAUGCGCCAUGUUGGUGUGCUGCACCCAUUAACUCAUCAUUUACAUUAGGUAUAUUUCCUAAUGCUAUCCCUCCCCCCUCCUCCCUCCCCCCACCUCUGGACACAGGAAGGGGAACAUCACACACCAGGAUUGUACGAUUUUAAACAGAGGAGGAACAGGUAGUAGUAUGAUCCAAUUUACCUUGUAAUUGAAUCUUGUUGGCAUGUAUGUAGAGAAUGAAGUAUGAGGGACUAGAGUAUCACAUAUUCAUUAGCCUUGUGCAGUCAGCCCUCUGAAUUCAUGGAUUCAACCAAACACAGAUUGAAAAUAUUUUUCUUAAAAAAACCAUCUGUACUGAACAUGUAGAUUUUUUUAUAAUCCCUAAACAAUACAGUCUAACAACUAUUUGCAUGGCAUUUACAUUGUAUUAGAUAUUAUAAGUAAUUUAGAAAGGAUUUGAAGUAUACAGAAAUAUGUGCCUAGGUUAUAUGCAAACACUGUGCCAUUUCAUAUCAAGGAUUUGAGCAUAAUCCAAGGAAGGUCCUGGAACCAGUCCCCCAUGGAUACUGGGGGACAGCCACAUAGGUUUUCCUGAUCUUUAAAUAGUCAUUAUUAGUCAUUGUCUCCACUUCUAAUAAGGUGGGUACUUAUGUUUUCAUUUUGUAAGAUAUGACAAAGGAGUAUCCUUUUCCUAUCAUUGUUACUCUGUAACCUUUAUACUCUUAACAUAUUUAUCUUAGUCUUCCAUGCCGGUGUAUAUAAAGACUCAUUUGCAGAUAUAGGUCCAUUUCCAAAUAGUUUGACUCAUUUUCAGUCUGGAGGGAGUAAGAAUGGGUAAAGACCAGCUCAAGAAUAGAUAUAGUUUAGAGCUUGAAAACUAAUUUUUAAAUGUAUACACACCUCACUCUAUUCAGUACAAAAAUAAGUUAAUGUAGUAAAUGUGUUCAAGAGAGACAUAGACUUUGUGGUCCGACUGUUUGGGUUUAUAUCCCAGCUCUGAGUGUCACGUCACGACUGUUUGCUUCUGUUUCUUCAUCUGUAAAAUGGGGAUAACAAUAAUACAACCGACUUCAUGGGUGUUUGUCUUAUUCUUAUAAUCACAUUGUUUUAUACUUUUUAAAAACCGUGUUUAAGGGCUCAGAAAGUGUUAGCCGUUAUUGUUAAUAAAAUUUGUUGAGAAAUUUGUAAAAAUUGCUUUUCAUGUUAGAUACCAGUGGGAACUUUAAAGCUUCAUAUGUUUUUAAAGUCGCACUUUUUAAUGAGUAAUAGCAAUAAUAAUGACAAUAAUUUUCAUUAUAAUGCCUGUUGUGUGGCAUACUCUUAUUAGCUUGUGUUUUUGUCACUGGUGUCUCCACUUUACAGAUGAGCAAAUUAAGUUCAUAGAGAGGUAAAUGUCUUGCUGAAAGUAAAAUGUCUUGUGGAGGAUAAUACAGCUAGGCAGCGGUCAGAGUUAGGAUUAAUCCCCAGUCCCUCCACAUGUGUCUCAUUUUACCAAGAAGAAAAUCAAGGUUUAGUGAAAUUAAAUAGCUCAUCCGGAGCAUCUAGUAUAUCAAUUAAGAUUUUUAUUGUUUCAAGUAAUAAAAGAUACAGCCAAAUGGUUUAAGCAGUAAAGAAGACCUAAAAAUUGGGCAGGUUUCAAGGUUCGUUGGGCUUACUUAGGUAUUGCUGUGCUUUGGGGGCGAUGUGGAAAAGAGUAAGCAGAGGCUCCCUGUGGUCUCUAGAUUCUUGCCCAGUGCUCCUUCCAAGAUGCUUUCCCAUAGUAUCAUAAAGAUCCUCAGCAUAGAUAGAUGAUUAAGGAUGCUAAAACUUCAUUCAUUCAACUCUUACGGAAUUUAUAUUAUUUACCCAUUAUGUACAUUUGUUAAAUUUAGUAAAACUUAAAUUUUGCAUAUACAUACUUUGGGUAGGGGUGAAAACUGGUACAACCAUUUUUAUGGCAAUUUGACAAUAUGUAUCAAAAUUAUAAGGCACAUAAUCCUUAAUACACCAAUCUUAUUACUAGGAGUUUGUUUUACAAAUAAGCUUGAUCAGAUUUGAAAAUGUGUAUGUAUGUGCGUACUAUAUGUGAUAUUGUUUAUAUAGCAAAAAAUGAAAAUCCAAAUAUUUCUCAAUAGGAACCCAUGUGUGUUUUUAAAUGAUACAUAUGCAGACAUACAUACACACAUGCAUGCGUUUGUUGGUAGCCUAGAGAGAUAACUCUUACUCGGAAGUGGGAGAGGGAUGACAUAAGUUGUGCUGUAUAGCUUUCUGUAAGUCUUAUCUUGUAUAAAAUGCAAAAUCUCUUGAGACAGUAUAACAAAAUGAACCCUGUCAUUUCCUGACUCUGUAAUCUCGCUCAAAUUUGUUUAAAGUCUCUGUACUUCAAUUCCCUUAUUUCUAAACUAGGGUUGAUAAUAGUAUCUACCCCAUAGGAGUAAUAAGAGAAUUAGAUUAAUUAGUACAUGUAAAGCACGUAAGACAGCGUCUGGCAUAGAGUAAGUAGUCAAAAUGUUAGCUAAAUUAUUAUUAUAGUUUCUAAAGAGAUGUGGGUAUUGAGUGUUUAUCAGCUAUGUCAAAUAUGUGUUCUGAGCUUUUGCAAGGUAGCCUUCAAGAAACAAUUACGCUAAGUCAGUCAGUCUACUUUUCUGAGGAGUAAUCUUCAAAUACCAACAUCAAAUAGAUUAUUAUCUAAUCUCUGGGAUAAAAAAUGGCCUGAUUUUCAAAGUAUUUGUUGCCAAUAAAUUGGAAUGACCAUGUGGCAAUCCAAUUUGGAUGGUAAAUAAGUCACAAUAACUGAUUUGAUCAUGCUGAGCCUGGAUAUUUUAGAUGCUAGCUAUGGCCAAAGCCAUGAAUAAAAAGGAAACAUUUACUUGUUCCAGAAACAUCCUGGGGAAAUCUUUGAAAAGCUCUUUUGACAUUGAAAAGGGCCUAUACAUAGUGUUAUUCUACAUAGUCUGAUAUAUUUUAGUAUAUUCAUGAUAUGUUCUUUGCAUAAUAAUAUACUUAUCCUGCAAUUUUUGAAAACCUACUAGAAUUCAAGAUGUACUGUGGUGAAUUUUAUGAUGGGAAAAAAAUACAGAAUUGCUGCAAAGAUUAAAUAAGAUUUCUUAAACAUAUAGUCUAACAUAACAAACAUUAACAAAUAUUAUUUUUCUUCUCAUUUAUAUCUUGGAAAAAAUGGAAACAUAGUCUUGUUUUAUAAACAUCCUGGAAAAAUUACUGAAAAGUGAAUUGGAAAAUAUAAAGGGCCUGUAGAUAGUAUUAGUCUCUAUAGUCAAGAUUUAUUUCAGCAUACUUAUAAUACUGUGGCAUCUGAGUAAAUAUCUUGCAAUUUUAGGAUAAACAUUGGAAUUCAUAAUAUAGUAUAAUGAAUUUGUUAGAUUAAAAAAUAUAGGAGACAUGCAUGGUAGUCUUAAGUUCCAUCAUUACUAACUGUUAGAGACCACAUGUUUUUGUAAGGUUAAAUGAGGAAAUAUAUACUAAGACUUUUAAGCUCUUUUGGAAUAAUAGACUAAUUAAACUAUUAGAUCUGGACCUCAUUCAGGGUACUGUUUCUAAUUUGGUUUCUAACUUCAGAUUCUCUGGUUUAUGAGAUAAAGAUUAGGCUAUUGUAAAACAGUGUAGGAUUGGAAAAAAGGGGGGGCCCUUAUUUCCUUGAAGAGGUUAUUUCUGUAGUCUUCCAAAUCAAAAGUAGAGAAUGUUAGAGGGUUAUUACUUAAUUCAAUAUAAUAAUUUCAAUUAUCAUGAGUCAGUAUUGUUAAAGAAAACCAGAGCUCGACAGUAAAGUGGUAAAAACAGAUUUUAGUAAGGCUCUAUUGCAAUAGUAUAGAACUGGGCUCAAUUCUGAAUAUAGUAAAGAAUGUUGGGGAUUUAUAGCUAAGGAGCAGAGUGGGGCAGAGGAUAGAAUCAGUGGAUGGAAAAUUAUUAAGAGGAAGCUUCAAGAGUAAGGGGAUUAUUGCCGAACCAACUAAACAGUGCCUUGCUGAAGGCAAGCCAUGUUGACCAGAUUAUCAAGGGUAGGGGGAUUCUCACUAAACUGAGUUAGCAGGAUUCUUGCUACAACUGGGCCAGGAGGCGUGAGGACAAGGCCCACGCAAGAACGUUGAAAAGAGGUAUCAGAGGAACCUGACUAAAGUUUGGUUAAGGGGUGAGCCUUUGCCACUGCGUAUAUGUUGAACACCUAAAAGGCGGCAUGAAUUAUCAAACAAAUAAUCCUUUUGUGAUAUUUGCACACACUGGAUUUCAAAAUAAUUAAACCUUCUCUUUUUAUAUUUAACCUGUGAGGUUUUAGACAAGAAAGUAAUUUUCUAGUUUUUUUUCUUUUCAUAUUUGAAUGGAAGUCACUCAUACAAAGUGAAAGUUUUAUUUAUAGUAUUGUAGUGUUUAUUUAUAAAAGGAUUAUUUGUAGUAAGUGUAGUAUUACUGUAUGUAUUCUUUUGAAAUAUAGUAGCCUUGUCUUCCUACCUCUAUUCAGCCACCACUAGGGAAAGUUUGCGAAAGUGCCCAAAUGACCCUUAAUGAAGAGAGAGCCAAAAUAACAAGUCAUUGAUACUUUUAAGAUGAAGUGGUUUCAUUUCUGUCAGGUUAGAUGAUUUGCAAGGUUAUGAUGAAAAUUGGAAUGGAAGAAAAACAAUAAGAAAAAUAUUUUUAAAAGUCAAAUAAGAUAAAAUAAGUUGCUUGUCACAAGAAAGUGAUUUCAGUUUCCCUUAUAAAGACAAAGUUAUCAGAAUGUAUAAAAAGCAUUUCCAGGGAGUGUUAUUUAUAAUAGAUGCUUCUAAACAAAUUGAGAGGAAGCUUACAAAUAAAGGAAUGAAAAAUAUAUACCAAAUAAAUGUUGAGAAAAGGAUAGUAUUAUUUGCAAUAAUAUUAAACACAAAUAAAAAAGUUUUAUUUGAUAUUUUAUGCAGAUACAAUUCAUGAAGUAGAUGUUAACGAUUAUUGCUUUUUUAUGCAUGAGACAACAUGGCAUCAAAAUGUAUAAAGUUAUCCAAGAGAAAAGAAAACAUAUGUUCACACCAAAACUUGUACAUGUAUGUUCAUAGCAGCAUUAUUCAUAAUAGCCAAAGAGUGAAAACAGUUUGAUGUUCAUCAGCUGAUGAGUGGAUAAAUAAAAAGUGAUAUAUUCGUAUUAUUUGGCAUUAAAAAUAAAUGCUUUCAUGAUCCAUGGUGAACCUUGAAAACGUUACACUAAGUGAAGGAAACCAGUCACAAAAGAACAUAUGUUAUACAAUUGCAGUUAUAUGAAAUGUCCAGAAUAGGCAAGUAAUCUAUAGAGACAGAAUGUUAAUUGGUGGUUACCUAAGGGAAAGGGGUCACCAACGAUGGUAUAGGUAGUGAAUGCUUAAGGGUAUAGGGUUUCAUUUUGGGGUGAUGAAAAUGUUCUAAACUUAGAUUAUGCUGACAAUUGUACAACUCUGUGAAUGAACUAAAUCCAUUAAAUUGUACUUAUAUCUCAAUAAGGAAGUUUUUUAAAAAUAAAAACUUCAUAUAGUAAACAUUAGCAAUGAAAGGGAAAGUUGAUGAAUUUAUAUUUAACCCAUUUAUGCCAGAGGCUACAAAUUUUUUCAUGUCAAAAAUCAGACCUUGGCCAUGACCUUGAGCAGUAGGAUAUAAAUAACUCCCACAAGCUUAGCGUUCCAAUAGUGGAACACUAGGCAUAAAUGAGUUAAGGCAGAUUUCAUGCCUCAUAAAAUGAACAGCUCAUUAAAGGAUAUGGAUAAUUUGAAUAAUAAGCAAUUAAACUUAACUCAUUAUAUUUCAGAAUUGCUAAAAUACUUGGAAUGUUCUAAACAAAAAGAAAUAAGUGUUUGAGGUGAUGGAUAUCUCAGUUACCCUGAUUUGAUCAUUACAUAUUAUAUGCCUGUAUCCAGAUAUUACAUAUACCCCAUAAAUAUGUAAAGUUAAUAUGUGUCAAGUUUUUAAAAGCUUAAUUCAGCCGAGUGUAGAACCUCAUACUGAAAAACAUAAGAUUUCUUAUACUUGUAUUGUUUUCCAGCACUUGUGAACUGUUUAUAAAAGUUGAUUAUAGGCCAGACGUUGUGGCUCACGCCUGUAAUCCCAGCACUUCGGGAGGCCGAGGCGGGCAGAUCAGAGGCCAAGAGAUCGAGACCAUCCUGGCCAACAUGGUGAAACUCCAUCUCUACUAAAAAUACAAAAAUCAGCUGGGUGUGGUGUCAUGUGCCUGUAGUCCCAGCUCCUUGGGAGGCUGAGGCAGGAGAAUCCCUUGAACCCGUGAGGCAGAGGUUGCAGUGAGCCAAGAUCAUGCGGCUGCACUCCAGCCUGGUGACAGAGCAAGACUCCAUCUCAAAAAAAAUAUAAAUAAAUAAAUAAAAAUAAAAAAUUUUAAAAAGUUGAUUAUAUAGUUGGCCAUAAAGAAAUCUCUGUACAAUGCACAUAUUUUUCAUUGAAAAUCAAAAUAGAAUCUAACAACAAAGAAGAUAGGGAGAAAUUUCUUUUCUACUUCUAAAAUUUUAAAGUUUUAAAAUAACUUUUUAAAAUAACUUUUGGGUUAAAACAGAAACCAAAAUUGAAAAAAAAGUUGGAAAUUAACAUGUAUUAUGUAUUAAAACUUAUGAAAUGUAGCCAAAGUGGUACUCUAUGGAAAAGUCAUUACCUUGAAUACUUUUAUUAGAAAACAAGAAGUACUGAAAAUAAAUGAACUAAUAAGGAGAUCGAGGAAGACAUAGUAAACAUGAAGUAAUCAAUAAAGUUAAAAGGGAAAAUGAAUAAGCAAAAAACUAGUACUUGAUCAGUAAAGCCAGUUUCCUUGAAAAGACUAAGAUAAUAGAGCAAUCUUUGAUAGAAGUGAUCAAAAUGAAAAAGAGGGAGUGAGAAAAGAUAACAUACAGAACAUACAGAACAAGAAAUUAGUCACUAAUCUUUUUAUUAUAAGGGAAUACAGCAUAUAGCUUUAUAGCAAAACAAUACACACAAAAAAACCUUGAAUGAGAUGGAAGAAAACUGCUGUAAAUUUGACUCAAGAAAACUUAAAAUUAUGACUAGCCUGGUAACCAUAGAAAUCAAAGAUCUCCAAGAGUCAUCAGACCUAGAUGAUUUUACAGGCGAGUUUUAGCUAAACUUACAAGUAAUAAUUAUAAUAAUAGUAGUAGUAAUUAAAGAUAAUAUUUUUUGAGCUGUUACCCUAUUCUAGACAGUGUUAAGUAAUUUACCUAUAUGAGCAAAUUUAAUCUUCACAGCAAACUUAGUGGAUAGUCAACAGUCUCUGUGUGAACACUUUCAGUGAUAGUGAGCUUUCUUCUUUGUAACAUAGCCUGCUCCUUUGUUCAGUAGUUUUAACUGUCAGUUCUCUAAUUUACAUGGAUGGAAAUGUCCUCCUUUAUUGCUCCUACCCAUUAGUCCUAGUUCUGCCUUGUAGAACUAUACGACAUAAAUUAACCUCUUCUUUCACGUGGCAGUCUUUUAUAUCCUGGAAAGCAGCCAUGAUGUCUACUUUUCUGUAGCUUAAAAGACUUUAUUUACAGCCUGUCUGAUACCAAGAUGGUAGUACAGCUGUGUUAUUUUCAUCAUCUUCUGCUCUAGUAACCAUAUGAAAAUGGGCAUGAGAUUACUUUGAAAUUACUCUUCCUUGUGACCCCUUAUCAACUUUCAGUGAGCAUUUUUUUUCUUUUGAGAAAUUGAAUAGAAACUCCUAGUGUCCACAUUUUGACAUCCUUUAGUCCUGUAGUUCUGUGAAGUUCCUGCAUGGCUUUACAGAAACUGUUAUUGGUAGUUUCAUGUUCAUGUCUUCCUGUCCUUUUAGAAUUCUGAAAGGUAAAUUGUGUGGGUCUGGAUUUUGAUUAUGUGUAUUUUAACUUGUCCUCAAAACUUGGUCUUUAAUGUCCUCUUAAUGAUGUUUAUUAAAUAUAAUUUUCUUAAUGGAGAACAUUAAAGCAAAAUCAGAGUUGUCUUAAUUUGUUUAGGUUGCUAUAAGAAAAAACCUCUGGGACUGGGUAAUUCAUAAAGAACAGAAAUCUAUUUUCUCACAGUUCUGGUGGCUGGGAAGUCUAAGAUCAAGGCACCAGCAGGUUUGGUUGUCUGGUGAGGGCUGCUGUCUGCUUCCAAGAUAACACCUUGUUGCUGCAUCUUCCAGGAGGGAGGGACAUUUCGUCCACACCUGAGGGAAGAUGGAGGUGUGACAUAACCUAACUCUGUAGCCUCUUUGAUAAGGUCUUAAUCCCAGCCACAAAGGGAGGAGCCUUUAUAUGGCUUAACUACCGCUUAAGGGUUCUACCUCUUUCUACUGUCAUACUGGCCUUUAAAUUUCAACACCUGAAUUUUGGAGGACACGUUCAAACCAUAGCACCAAGGGUUGAGUAAUGGAUUGUUCUGUCUCUUACUUAGAGCAGGAUAUUGUUAAACAUGGCAGACUUUGGAGUCAGAUAUACUUGGUUGAAACCGUGACUUUGCUACUUAUUAACUGUAUGACCUUGGCCGUGUCACUUGACUACUCUGAGUAUGUUUUGUUACCUGUAUUGUAUUAUUGGUAUUUCUGCAUCACAGAGUAUUGUAUGGAUUAAGUAAGAUAUCAUGGCCGGGAAUGGUGGCUCACACCUGUAAUCCCAGCAAUUUGGGAGGCCAAGGUGGAGGAUUUCCUGAGCUCAGGAGUUUGAGAAUAGCCUGGGCAACAUCUCAAAAUCCUGUUUCUACUAAAAAUACAAAAAAAAUUAGCUGGGUGUGGUGGCAUGCACCUGUAAUCCCAGCUACUCGGGAGGCUGAGGCUGGAGAAUCGCUUGAACCCGAGAGGUGGAGGUUGCAGUGAGCUGAGAUAGCACCACUGACAGAGUGAGACUCUGUCUCCCUGCCAAAAAAGUAAUUAAUUAAAUAAGAUGUGUGUCAAGAACUUAGUAAAGAGUUUAGCUCGUAGAAGGUGAUUCAUAAAUGAAAGCUUAUAAUAAAAUCACUACAUAAUUUAUCUUUCCCAUGCAGCAGAUCUGUCCUGUCCUUGUCUGUUUUUUAAUUCUAAAAACAUCCCAGCAAUCCUUUUUGCUAUCUUCAAAACAUAGCUCUUCUCAACUGGGGCUCUAUUCUUCGUGGACAAUAUUGUUAGAUGGUUUUCUACUCUUCAUCUUUGAUUAUGGUUUUCUACUCUUCAUCUUUGAUUAUUUCCCCCUCUCUUUGUAUAUUUCUUUUUCAGGCACAAUCUGUCUUUAUCAAAAAAUUUCUGAUAUGGCAAUAUUUUUUUAGAUGCUUCCAUAUGUUUAUGAUUGUAUAAAUUGCUUUUUAUUUUAUUUAUUUAUUUUUUUGAGACUGUAUCUCACUCUGUCACCAGGCUGGAGUGCAGUGGCACAAUCUCAGCUCACUGCAACCUCCGCCUCCCAGGUUCAAGUGAUUCUCCUGCCUCAGCCUCCUGAGUAGCUGGGAUUACAGGCGUGCACCACCAUGCCCAGCUAAUUUUUGUAUUUUUAGUAGAGACGGGGUUUCACCAUGUUGGCCAGGAUGGUCUCGAUCUCCUGACCUUGUGAUCCGCCCGCCUCGGCCUUCCAAAGUGCUGGGGUUACAGGCGUGAGCCACCGCGCCCGGCCAUUGCUUUUUAUUUUUAAUCUAUACCCUCAAACCAUAUUCUCUUUUAAAAUUAUUGACCAUGGGCUCAUAGCUUCUUUUCUCUACAUUUUUAAAGAAAUGUUUGCCUAAAUCUGAAGUGUUGAAUUGACGGUCCAGCAUUCCUUUUAGUGCUGUGACCAAUGAAGGGUCAAACCAAGGACACCUAGGACCUGAGAUGGAGAAGGCAAGUUAGUAAGAUAACAGUGUGGUAGCACUCAUGAAGUAGAUGCAUAAGCAGACCCUAAAGAUUAGGGUGGAUCAGCAGUAGGGUAAUUGUUAGGUGUCACAGGAAGUAAGUGGAACCUGUUAAUCCAAGGGAAUCUAGGGGGAGGCAGUAGGCAAAGUUCCAGGGAGGACAAGUAGUCAGCACCAAGAAAAAUGUCUAACAUUGAGGUCACUGUGUAAGGUAAUGUUGUUUUUCAACAGAUCUUUAUGGAAUGUCUGUAAUGUGGCAGGGUUAAGGCUCAGAACUCUAGGACCCAAAGAACUGAUAGGGUCACACUGGUCAAGAACCCAGCUGAACGAAGAACCCGUUUAGAGUUCUACAUAGUCAUUUGUAAACUCUGGGCAGAUUAGUUCUUUUUGAUCUUCUGUUUCUUCAUAUGUACAGUGAAGAUAAUAACACCUUAAGGCUGAGAGGAAUACAGAAAUGUGUGUAGAGUUUCUUUUUGUGCCAAGCACUUCUUGUGACAAACAAGGGGAAAUAAUAAAAAGAAUCCUAACAUGUGAAAAAGUUGUCAAUCACUUGAUUAAUAUCCUUUUUAGCUCCUGUGUUGUGUUUCCAAGAAUUGGGUAUCAGUUUUAAACAUGGAAAAUACCAUGAAGAUUACAGAAAAAAAUCCUUCAUUGUCCAUCCUUCUUCUGUGACCUUCCCCAGAAAACUCACCAUGAUUUAUGCCAUGGUCCCUAGGAAGUCUAAUUUUUUUACUUAAUUGACCUUGUCCUUCUUUACUUGCUUAACUUCCCACCUGCUAUGGAAUGUGAGCAGUUUAGAAAGUGGCAAAUGUGGAAUUUAAGGGCUAAACAAUUUUGGCCAUGAGGAAUACUUUUCAGUCACAAAGCAUCACAAAAGUCAAAUAAAUAUCCACGAUUCAAAAGAAAGCCUUAGUAACUCUCUAAACAGGAAAUAAAUUAUAGUAUGGGAUAAUAUAAAGCUUAGAACAGAAUAUAUGUUCACAUUAUAACAACAGAAAUUUUUAUAAUGCUAAACUAUAUAUUUAUUCUCAUUAUAGAAAAUUAUGCACCCAAAUUGACAUUCAGCCCAUAAGAGUAAUAAACACGUGGCAUGGCAGAGUAACUCCCUCUCUUAGAGGAGGAUUUUAAACACCAGAGGGCAGAGUGUUCCAGAGGACAUUUUCAGUUCAGCUGGCCUUUCUUAAUUGUAAAUGCGCAUCCUUACCUUGUCCGUCAGUCAUUCAUGUCGUGGGCAGAAUUUCAAAAGUUAAGAAAUGUGGUUAUUUCAUUUUACUUAUUUUUUUCUUAAGACACAGAGUCCUGCUUUGUCACCCAGACUGGAGUGUGGUGGCACAAUCACUGCUCAUUGCAGCCUCAACCUCCUGGGGUCAAGAGAUCUUCCCACCUCAGCCUCCUGAGUAGCUGGGACUACAGGCGUGCACCACCAUACCUGGCUAAUUUUUUCAUUAUUUUGUAGAGAUGGGGUCUUGCUAUGUUGCCCAGGCUGGUCUAAAGUCCUGGGCUCAAGCAACCCUCUCACCUCGGUCUCCCAAAGCACUGAGAUUACAGGUGUGAACCACUGUGCCCAGCCAAGAAAUAUGGUCAUUUUAGAAUUGUCUAUGUGGUAUUAUCUGUUUUGAUGACUUUGUUUAGAUAGCACAAUGAGCAGUGUUUUGAGUUAUACCAGAGUUGGUUGAACAUCUCUGUUUUCCCCAUUUCUGGUUAAUGUUCAUGUUUCUGAUUUCUGAAAACGAUUUUUAGAAAAAAUUAUGUAUACAUCUAUAUCAUUCAGUAAAUUUUAUAACUUUAGAUUAAUGAAGUAAGUAAAGUGAGAGAAAGGAGAUUUGAUAUGUGUAUCUUAUGGCUCAGUAUGCCCUUUUAUGCCCUGCUUAUCAAUAAAAACAUUCUGAAAGAACCACCUGCCAACUCAUGACCUUUUUCAAAUGUUACAAUUAUCAUUUAGAGGUAGCAUCACACAUUUGGGAUAAUUUUAUUCAGGGUUUAGAUAGUAAAGUCAACAUAUAAAAUAAAAACUGAGUAUAAAGAAAAUUAUCCUCAGAAAUCCAUUACAUAUCAUUCACGACAUUCAUUAAACAGAAAUACUGCUUCUCAGUAUAUCCAACCCUGCCAGUUUAUCCUUUAGAGUUGUAACUAUUUUACUCUUUACUCUCUUUUUCUUUGACCACCAGAUGAAGUAGUUGGCUGAUGUAUAGGGAUCACAUAUAUGAUUUUUAAGAAUAUAUUUCUUUUUCUUCUCUGUCACUCAUUACCCUACUGCUGCAGAUUGAAGUCCUGAUCUGAAGCAGUAGCCAUUGCUAGGAAAGACACAACCCCGCGUAGAAAGUUGGCCAAAGCUUGAAUUGCUAUAGCUAGUAGAAUGGUUACUUUCUUAACUCCUGUGAGAAUAGAGAUUUCGUAUGUACAUCUCUUCAUAAAUAUUACCCUACCUUUAAGCACAAUAGAGUUUAGCACGGAUGAUUACUCCUUAGAGAAAGCUUUUAAUAUAGCAAGACUGAAAAAAGAAUAAAAAUAAAAAAGAAUGUAAAACUGUAUAAGUUUUAGCAUGACUUACCUAAAUUAAUCAUAAAGGAGUUAAAAAUUAGUAACCAAGGGGAAGAGCUUAACUCCUUAAAUCUCUCUCCACCCUUAAGUUAAAUCCAAUUUUUCAAGCAAAACAAAACCUGUGUACUUUGUCUUUUGAAGUAUUUUAAUCAUGUCCUCAUCCCAGUUAGCUCCUACACAGCAUAAGCAACGUUAGAAAAAAUUAUUUGUUGUCCAAGUUUACAUUUUUUGCAGAACUUUUCUGGUAUCUCUCUAAUGCAAAGAUCUGCUCAACAUGACUUGAUGAUGGGGAGGUGGGAGAGAAAGUUGCUCUUUUUACCUAAGAUAUUGAAUAAUUAGUAUUCUAAAAAGUCACAACUGAAGAGAAUUUCCCUCAAAAAUAACUACUGGCACAAGACAAUAUUUGAGUUAAAAAACUUACUAGGUAGAAGAGAUUAGAUUAUCCAGGAAACAGAAUGAGAUAGGCUGUCCAUGGAAUUUCCAAGUCAAACAUAAUAGCUCAUUUUUGAGUUUGCCCUACAGUUUUCUAGUUAGGUAGGAUAAAAAGUAAUAGGUUAUUUUAAACAACUCAAUCACUUUGCAUGUUCUUUGAUAUUAACCAUUCCAUAGAAACCACUUAUACUUCUUUAUUACCAAGUUACUAUUUUCUGAAGACAUUUAUAAGUCAUGUUGAGGCAGUAGAAUUACUUGUACAUUAUUAUAUUAAAUAAUCCUUGAACGCUAGUCCGCAGUAUCUGUAUCUACUAUAAUUCUAAAAAGAAAUAGCUACUAGCUACUUGUGAAAAGUAUAUGCAGUGUGAUGGGACACAAUAUCCAGUCAAACAUAAAACCUAGCCUGGAAAAAUAUUUACCCUUUCAGGCAAUUUUCUGUGUUUAUGGAGUUCUAUUGAAAUUCCACUUUUCAUUUUUCUUUGCUGUUUUGCUUAGAUACUAUUAAAAAAGAUAAUAUAGAUGUUUAGAAUUUUAAGCCUUUGCUUUGUAUUUAUUUUUUUCUAUUCCCACAGUAGCUUUAGGAAUAAGGUAGAAAAUGCUUUACUGAGAUGAAUCAGUGGGUCAGAGUAGUUAGGUGCCUUACUCAGGGUUAUAUUUAGAAGUAGCAAAGCUGUUAGUCCAACUACAGUCAAGACUAGUCAAAUGCAUGUCCAUCCCACUACAUUGCAAUUCUUUUUAGUCACAUUUUACUGAGGUUCUUCAUUUAUGGAGAUAAAUGCAUCAUAAAUCUAUGACCAACAAAUACGUAACUUUUCCAGAAUUGGUAUUAUAAUGGCAGUGUUGCCCAUGUAAGAGAAUGGUAUAAUAGGUAAAUUUACCUAAUAUUUUGCUUUGUAUUGUAUCUGAAUAUUGCAUUAAAUAAAUGGUGAUGGAAAAGUAACACAGAGAUAUGAUAUAGAACAAUUUCAUAUAGAACUACCCUAUAUAAAUAGAUGAAAUAUCAUAGCAUCAGUGACCCAUGCUUAAUAAAUCUAAUGAAAGAUAUUUUUCUGCACCAGUCAUCUCAGAGCAACAUCCAGAAGACUAUAGAGAGAGUACCAUUACGACAAUUCUAUGCAUUGGUGCUUUCACUGGCUCCCUCUUCUCCUGUGAUACCGUUUGGAAGCUAUCCUACUAUCCCCUGGAAGGGGGAGCUCUUCCUAAUUCCUGGGAGGUGAGGGAAAACUAUGACAAGAAAACGAUUGUCCAGGCCCAGUUAGGGAGAGGCCUUUAGAAGCAUGGAGUGGACCAGUAACCCUGUCUUACAAGUGAUUGACGGAGAAGUUUUCUUGUUCAUGAAUGAAGGCUAUGAGCAUUUUUAGUGAAGUAAGUGUCUUUUGAAACUUUCUUUAUCUAGAAGGAAUACAGGUGAUAGUAUGCCUCUCUUUGAAAUUGGUGUCAUUGCUACUUUAUUAGUCAAUCAGUUGAUAGUGCUGCAGUUUUGGCAUAUCUGAUGCAUACCAUCUGAAUGAAAGGCAUUUAAUUAGGGUUUUAAUAUCUCUAAGUAUUUAAAAAUGAAUUUUCUGCUAUCUCAAACUCUAGACAGUUCCUUACAUUGCAACAAAAUCACUGUAUAAUUUUAACACUUAAUAAAUUAUGGAGAUACUGCAGACCUAUAUUAGCUUGCUAAAGUAUUAAUAUUUUAAAUUACCUCAAUUGCAUUUUUUGUUGGUGCCUACUAAGUAACUGUUUUACAGCGUAUAUUCACACAGCUCUGAUUCAGAAAAUCAGAAGAGCAAAACAUGAGAAGGAAACAGUAAGAGAGGAGUUUACAGCUUUAAGGCAUGAGGAGCUUACAGCUUUUUAAUAUAAAUUGUUCCCAGAAUCCAUGUCACAGAUCCUUAUAUGGUGCUGCUUUUUUCCUCUUGGUUGCUAUGACAACAGCAGCACUGCACCAUUCAUCAGCUCUGGACCUGGGCUGCACUGCUAGCCUUCCUUGUUACUCCUGAAUGUUAAGAAGAACAUCCGUGAAUCAUUCACUCUGUUAACGCUGCGCCAUUAGAAACCUAAGAACCAGUUCUUCCAGUAAUUUGCUCUAACAGAGGGUGAACUAAACUGCGCCACAGAGAAAAAUUGUGUAAAAAUAUUUCUUUUAUCCUAAUGGAAUCAUACAACCUAUAUUUGCUGCAGUAUUCUGAAAGGACAAGCUUAUGUCAACCAAUCUAAUGAAAAGAACUCGUCUGUGUAAUCUCUUGAAAUCAUUAGUUGUUCAAAACAGAAUACCACAGUGCUUCUCUGGAUACAAAAAGAAGCAGGUGAUGUUGUUAGGGGUUCUAAACCCCUUUGGGAGCAUCUCUUGUGCUUUGGGACCAUAAUCAACAUCUGCUAUAAGAAGUAUCACCUGUAACGCACAGUGAUGCUGAACAGGAGCUUGGCCCCCCUCCAUCUGUAGAUGAGGCAGCAAACACACUCAUGACUCGUCUGGGUUUCCUCCUUGGAGAGAAAGUCACAGAAGUUCAGCCAGGUGACCAAUACAGCAUGGAAGUACAGGAUGAAAAUCAGACCUCAGCAAUCACCCAGCGGAUAAGUCCUUGUUCCACUCUGACUAGCAGCACUGCCUCUCCACCAGCCAGUAGCCCCUGCUCUACACUCCCACCCAUCAGUACAAAUGCAACUGCCAAGGACUGCAGCUAUGGGGCUGUUACUAGUCCAACCUCUACCCUUGAAAGCAGAGAUAGUGGCAUCAUUGCUACAUUAACAAGCUAUUCUGAAAAUGUGGAACGCACAAAAUAUGCUGGGGAAAGCAGUAAAGAAUUAGGAUCUGGAGGAAACAUAAAACCUUGGCAGUCUCAAAAAUCCAGCAUGGACUCCUGUUUGUAUCGAGUAGAUGAAAACAUGACUGCUUCCACCUAUAGUCUGAAUAAGAUCCCAGAGAGAAAUUUGGAAACAGUGUUAUCUCAAUCAGUACAGUCUAUUCCUUUGUAUCUCAUGCCACGGCCAAAUUCAGUAGCAGCCACCAGCUCUGCCCACUUGGAAGACCUUGCUUACCUGGAUGAGCAGAGACAUACACCUUUGAGAACUUCUCUACGAAUGCCAAGACAGAGCAUGGGUGGUGCUCGCACACAGCAGGAUUUAAGAGUUCGCUUUGCACCUUAUAGGCCUCCAGAUAUCUCCUUGAAGCCUCUGCUCUUUGAAGUGCCCAGCAUCACUACAGAGUCAGUGUUUGUUGGCCGAGAUUGGGUUUUCCACGAAAUAGAUGCUCAACUUCAAAGUUCAAAUGCCAGCGUGAACCAAGGAGUAGUGAUUGUGGGAAACAUUGGAUUCGGCAAAACUGCCAUCAUCUCCAGACUGGUGGCCCUCAGCUGCCAUGGUACAAGGAUGAGACAGAUCGCCUCAGACAGCCCACAUGCCUCCCCCAAACAUGUGGAUGCCAACAGAGAGCUGCCACUCACACAGCCACCUUCAGCCCACUCAUCUAUCACCAGUGGAAGCUGCCCAGGAACUCCGGAAAUGCGCAGGCGGCAGGAGGAGGCUAUGCGAAGACUAGCCUCGCAGGUGGUUGCCUAUCACUAUUGUCAAGCAGAUAAUGCCUACACUUGCUUGGUGCCAGAAUUUGUCCACAAUGUUGCUGCCUUGCUCUGCCGCUCACCUCAGCUGACAGCCUAUCGGGAGCAGCUUCUUCGGGAACCUCACCUGCAGAGCAUGCUGAGCCUUCGUUCCUGUGUUCAAGACCCCAUGGCCUCCUUCCGGAGGGGAGUUCUGGAGCCACUAGAAAAUCUCCAUAAAGAGAGAAAAAUCCCAGAUGAAGAUUUCAUCAUUUUAAUUGAUGGAUUAAAUGAAGCAGAAUUUCACAAACCGGAUUAUGGGGAUACAAUUGUAUCGUUUCUGAGUAAAAUGAUCGGAAAGUUUCCUUCUUGGCUCAAACUAAUUGUAACAGUUAGGACCAGUUUACAGGAAAUUACCAAGCUGCUGCCUUUCCAUAGGAUUUUUUUGGAUCGACUAGAAGAGAAUGAAGCCAUAGACCAGGACCUGCAGGCUUACAUCCUGCACCGGAUACACAGCAGCUCAGAGAUCCAGAAUAACAUUUCACUUAAUGGCAAAAUGGACAAUACUACAUUUGGCAAACUCAGUUCUCAUCUCAAGACCCUCAGUCAAGGGUCCUAUCUAUAUCUGAAACUUACAUUUGACCUCAUAGAGAAAGGCUAUCUAGUGUUAAAGAGCUCUAGCUACAAAGUAGUUCCUGUUUCGCUCUCAGAGGUUUAUUUACUCCAGUGCAAUAUGAAGUUCCCAACCCAGUCUUCCUUUGACCGGGUGAUGCCUCUCCUGAAUGUGGCAGUGGCCUCUCUCCACCCACUGACUGAUGAGCAUAUCUUCCAGGCCAUCAAUGCUGGGAGCAUUGAAGGCACACUAGAAUGGGAGGAUUUUCAGCAGAGAAUGGAGAACCUCUCCAUGUUCCUAAUCAAGCGCAGAGACAUGACUCGUAUGUUUGUACAUCCUUCUUUUCGAGAAUGGCUUAUCUGGAGAGAAGAAGGAGAGAAAACCAAAUUUCUCUGUGAUCCGAGGAGUGGUCACACGUUACUUGCCUUCUGGUUUUCCCGCCAAGAGGGAAAACUAAACCGACAGCAGACUAUUGAACUGGGACAUCACAUCCUCAAAGCACACAUUUUUAAGGGUUUGAGUAAAAAAGUUGGUGUAUCAUCCUCCAUCCUCCAAGGUCUCUGGAUCUCUUAUAGCACAGAAGGUCUUUCCAUGGCACUGGCGUCUUUACGAAAUCUCUACACUCCAAAUAUAAAGGUCAGCCGACUGCUGAUUUUGGGAGGUGCCAAUAUUAAUUACCGGACAGAGGUUUUAAAUAAUGCUCCAAUUCUAUGUGUUCAGUCCCAUCUUGGUUACACAGAAAUGGUAGCCCUGCUGCUGGAGUUCGGGGCCAACGUGGAUGCCUCUUCUGAAAGUGGCCUGACUCCCCUGGGAUAUGCUGCAGCAGCAGGGUACCUGAGCAUUGUGGUGCUGCUGUGCAAGAAACGGGCCAAGGUGGAUCAUUUGGAUAAGAACGGGCAGUGUGCUUUGGUUCAUGCUGCACUCCGAGGUCAUCUGGAGGUUGUCAAGUUUUUGAUUCAGUGUGACUGGACGAUGGCCGGCCAGCAGCAAGGAGUAUUUAAGAAGAGCCAUGCCAUCCAACAGGCCCUCAUUGCUGCAGCCAGCAUGGGUUAUACUGAGAUUGUCUCCUACCUACUUGAUCUUCCAGAAAAAGAUGAAGAGGAAGUAGAGCGAGCACAGAUCAACAGCUUUGACAGUCUCUGGGGAGAGACAGCCCUAACAGCUGCAGCCGGAAGGGGCAAACUGGAGGUGUGCCGUUUGCUCUUGGAACAAGGGGCGGCAGUGGCCCAGCCAAACCGCCGAGGAGCAGUGCCACUAUUCAGCACAGUGCGCCAGGGCCACUGGCAGAUUGUUGAUCUUUUACUCACCCAUGGAGCUGAUGUCAACAUGGCAGACAAGCAGGGCCGCACUCCCCUGAUGAUGGCUGCUUCCGAAGGCCAUCUAGGAACCGUGGACUUUCUGCUUGCACAAGGUGCCUCCAUUGCUCUUAUGGACAAAGAAGGAUUGACAGCCCUCAGCUGGGCUUGUUUGAAGGGCCAUCUCUCAGUAGUACGUUCUCUGGUGGAUAACGGAGCUGCCACAGACCAUGCUGACAAGAAUGGCCGUACCCCACUGGAUCUGGCAGCUUUCUAUGGCGAUGCUGAGGUGGUCCAGUUCCUGGUAGAUCAUGGGGCCAUGAUCGAGCACGUUGACUACAGUGGAAUGCGCCCUUUGGAUAGGGCAGUGGGGUGCCGGAACACUUCUGUUGUUGUCACUCUUCUGAAGAAAGGAGCCAAGAUAGGUUGUCAGACGUUACCGAGUCGCCCACGAGGUCCAGCCACAUGGGCGAUGGCCACCUCCAAGCCAGACAUCAUGAUCAUCCUGUUGAGCAAGCUGAUGGAAGAGGGGGACAUGUUUUAUAAGAAAGGUAAAGUAAAGGAAGCUGCCCAGCGCUACCAGUACGCCCUGAAGAAGUUCCCUAGAGAAGGGUUUGGUGAGGACUUGAAAACUUUCCGGGAACUAAAGGUGUCUCUCCUCCUCAACCUCUCUCGGUGUCGCAGGAAAAUGAACGAUUUUGGAAUGGCGGAGGAAUUUGCUACUAAGGCCCUGGAGCUGAAACCGAAAUCUUAUGAAGCUUACUAUGCGAGAGCAAGGGCAAAACGCAGCAGCAGCAGACAGUUCGCAGCAGCCUUAGAGGACCUGAACGAGGCCAUCAAGCUGUGUCCCAACAACCGUGAGAUCCAGAGACUUCUGCUGAGAGUGGAAGAAGAGUGUAGACAGAUGCAGCAGCCACAGCAGCCACCGCCGCCACCGCAGCCUCAGCAGCAGUUGCCGGAAGAAGCAGAACCUGAGCCACAGCAUGAAGACAUAUACUCUGUACAGGAUAUAUUCGAGGAGGAGUACCUGGAACAGGAUGUUGAAAAUGUUUCCAUUGGCCUCCAGACAGAGGCCCGGCCCAGCCAGGGGCUCCCGGUCAUCCAGAGCCCACCCUCCUCUCCCCCGCAUCGGGACUCAGCCUACAUCUCCAGCUCACCUCUUGGCUCUCAUCAGGUUUUUGACUUCCGGUCCAGUAGUUCUGUAGGCUCUCCCACUAGACAGACCUAUCAGUCCACCUCACCUGCCCUUUCUCCAACUCAUCAGAACUCACAUUACAGGCCUAGCCCACCACACACUUCCCCGGCUCAUCAGGGAGGAUCUUACCGUUUCAGCCCCCCUCCUGUGGGAGGACAGGGCAAAGAAUACCCAAGCCCUCCCCCUUCCCCUCUCCGGAGAGGCCCUCAGUAUCGGGCCAGCCCUCCAGCUGAAAGUAUGAGUGUCUAUAGAUCCCAGUCUGGUUCACCCGUGCGCUAUCAGCAGGAAACAAGCGUCAGUCAGCUUCCUGGCAGACCCAAAUCUCCAUUAUCCAAAAUGGCCCAGCGGCCCUACCAGAUGCCUCAGCUCCCUGUGGCAGUUCCCCAGCAAGGGCUCAGGCUACAGCCUGCCAAGGCCCAGAUUGUGAGAAGUAACCAGCCCAGCCCAGCCGUCCAUUCAAGCACCGUCAUCCCCACAGGAGCCUAUGGCCAAGUAGCCCAUUCAAUGGCCAGUAAAUACCAGUCUUCACAAGGAGACAUAGGAGUCAGCCAGAGCCGGUUGGUUUAUCAAGGGUCAAUUGGGGGAAUCGUAGGGGAUGGAAGGCCGGUGCAGCAUGUCCAAGCCAGCCUGAGUGCAGGCGCCAUCUGUCAGCAUGGAGGAUUGACCAAAGAGGAUCUUCCACAGCGACCUUCCUCAGCAUACCGAGGUGGCGUGAGAUACAGCCAGACACCACAGAUCGGACGCAGCCAGUCAGCAUCCUAUUACCCAGUCUGUCACUCAAAACUAGAUCUGGAGCGCUCCUCCAGCCAACUAGGUUCCCCUGAUGUGUCGCAUUUAAUCAGAAGACCUAUCAGUGUCAACCCUAACGAAAUCAAACCGCACCCGCCAACUCCCAGGCCGUUGCUGCAUUCCCAAAGUGUAGGCCUUCGCUUCUCUCCAUCUAGCAAUAGUAUCUCCUCCACCUCCAACCUAACUCCGACCUUCCGGCCAUCUUCUUCCAUCCAGCAAAUGGAGAUCCCACUGAAACCUGCAUAUGAGAGGUCAUGUGACGAGCUGUCGCCAGUGUCUCCAACUCAAGGAGGUUACCCCAGUGAGCCCACCCGAUCCAGGACCACACCAUUCAUGGGGAUCAUAGAUAAAACAGCACGGACUCAGCAGUACCCCCACCUCCACCAGCAGAAUCGGACCUGGGCAGUGUCAUCUGUGGACACCGUCCUCAGUCCCACGUCUCCAGGCAACCUGCCUCAGCCUGAGUCCUUCAGUCCACCAUCAUCCAUCAGCAACAUUGCCUUUUAUAACAAAACCAACAAUGCACAGAAUGGCCAUUUGCUGGAGGACGAUUAUUACAGCCCCCAUGGGAUGCUGGCUAACGGGUCUCGUGGAGACCUCUUGGAGCGAGUCAGCCAGGCCUCCUCCUAUCCCGACGUGAAGGUAGCUCGGACUCUACCUGUGGCUCAGGCAUACCAGGACAACCUGUACAGGCAGCUGUCCCGAGACUCUCGGCAAGGGCAGACAUCCCCUAUCAAACCAAAGAGACCGUUCGUGGAGUCUAAUGUUUAAAAGACGUUUUGUUGGAGUGAGACCCAUAUGUUUUCACUGCACAUUUUCAGGCUUGGUUUCCACAUUCGAGGUAGUUCUCUGGCUUAAUUUCUCAUGUAGUUUCUGUGUGGUGUUCAGAGGUGGCAGCCCACAUGCUGAAAUCCUUUGCAUGCAGCCGACUGGGAAGCGGCCUCCCGGGAGCCAGGACUUCAGUUUCUCUUGUCUGUGCCCAGCCACAUGCUCUCUCCCUCUCUUCAGAUGCCAACGAGGAGAUUUUCGUGCUGUGUGCUUUAACCCAGGGAGAUCAGACACACUGGUCAGCUUUUUCCAGGAGACAAUCGCUUUCACUGAUGUUCUUGUUGUGUAAUUGUCUUUUUCCUUUUUUAAAAAAUAAGGUGUUCUUGUUCGUUUUCUUCUAGAAACUUUAGAAAGAGUGCGAUGCCCCUUUGCCUUUGCAUCCUUAGCCAGUGUCACCCACACAGCCAGCCGCAGCGCAUUCUCAUGCUGUGGCCCCUCCCCAGACCGCCAGCGCCCUGCAGCCACCAGGUCUGCAGUGUGCAUUAGGAUUAUUGCUGGUCUUCCUAGGGGGUAAAAGGAUCAGAGAGAGAAGAAUUAAGUGCUAAAUUGGAAGAAAACCCCAAUAUAAUUAUGUAAAAUGUCACUACAUUGAUUUUCCAAGAGGCAUUGUAGGAACAUGUCAAAAACAGCCAGCCCUUUAAAUAUUGCAGUCAGCCAAGGAAAUUAGAUGAGAAUUGUGGCUAUUAAGAGAAUUCACUGAGAGUUAUUCUCUAGAUUUUUAGCCGACAAUUAACCACUAAAAGCUGCUGCUUUUCCAGGGUGGGGGAGGGAAUGAAUACAUAGAAAAACAAAAAAGAUUGUUCUGGAUUCUCAGUGAAAGGCUAUAGGAAGUCUGUUCUGGAGACAUCUACUUUUUAGAUCCUGAUACAUCACUGAGUGUCAUACUCCACUAAAAGGAAACUCUAACCGAAGGCUGGCUGGUGUGACAAUCCCGUUAGUUGGAUCUUCACCUACAGCCAGAUUUUGUUCUAGUGGCCCUCUUCCUGUAAACCCAGAUGGUGUCAUACAGAAAUUGUUUCUUUCAGAAGCAGAUUGGAAUCUCUUGGGACCAUGAGACUGAGUCCCAAUAUUUCCACCCAGGGUCAUGCCCGUUGUUGUCUACUUCCAUUUUGAGAUCUAUAGUUUGAUUAUCUAUUAUUACAGGAACUGUUUCUUUUCUUUUUCUAGGAGUGUUUAUGAGAGUGUGAUAUUUUAAAGUCAGACGCAGCAAAAACUGUUUCAGGGUGAAGAAAGACCCCUUUCAGCCCUGUUUUGCAGCCCUGGGUGGGGGCAUGAGAUAGACAGCAAGCUUCUGAUCUUGAAGCUUGUCUAGAAGACACAUCUUCUAGGUCUCGUGGUCAUUUGGUAGGCUGACCUUUGAGUGAGCGAGGCCACUAUUGAGUGGAUAGCAAGAACAUUGGAACCAAAGCCUCGGCACAGGCCUGGCACUGGCUGUACAUCAGCUCUUACAACUAAACAACUCAACUAAGCAACUGAAACGAAACAAAGGAGCAUUCGUUCUCUGUUGUUAGGAAUCAUUCUGCUCUGUUAGGGAAGGGCUGCAGGAAGGGCAGUUUCCUGAAUAAAAAUCUGGCUGCGACCAGUCCCAUGUGUCUGGUAAGUAAGUAAGUAAGUAAGUGCCCUUUGAAGGGAUCAUUAAGACACAGGGAGCAUGAACCUGAGAUCAGAAGCAUUUCUUUACUAAUUUAGAUUCUGCGAAAUAGACGGACCUCUCCACCCCCAAACCUAAAACAGGCCAGGACUUGUCUCUGUGCUGAAAGCAAAUAGCAAGACUAACUCAAGCCCCAGCCUCUUUCCACACUCCCUGAUACCUAAGGACUGCUUUCUCAGCUAGACCAGGGUGGGCAUCAGCGACGCCUUCUCAGCUAGACCAGGGUAGGCAUCAGCGUCCUCUCUCCAUCUCUAUACCCCUCUCUCUCACAUCAGGAAGAUGAAAUGUGUAGCUCUAGCGGCAACCUCUAGCCAGGAGCCCAGUGGCCUCUCAGAUUGCUUUUUGGCCAGGUCUCAGCACUGCUGGCAUCUUUACAUCUUACUCCUUAAAACCGCCUCUCGCUGAGGAGCCACUGCAUUUUGAAGAAUUUCUCAGUGUCUGUCAGGAAAGUGCUCCUGCUCAUUUGGAACGCCACACACCACCCGCACUCACCUGUCCAGGCGAAUGAGCAGGUCCUGUAGCUUUACAAAUAUGCCGCUGAUGCCGCUUCUCCCCAGGGUCUCUCAGUUUUCCAGGACAAAAAGAUUUAGGGCCUAUACCCUAUGGGCAAAACACCUAAAAUGUCAACAGUCAAAAUGCCAUUCUUUUUGGCCAUCAUAAGAGGGAGUAGGUAUCACUGCUGCAUGCCAGUUGUUUUUGACUAGAAUAUGCCAACCAGAGCUUGUUGGGGCAGGAGACGUUUUUCCUUACAAGCAGACUGCCUGUGCCCUGUGCCCUGUUUGCUACUUCACUGCCAUGGAAUGAUCCGAGUACUGUAUUUCAGAGCUGCCCCUUCCCCAGCAGCAAACACUCGCUGAGUCCAUGUCUGGCUUCAGGUGGGAGGAAAUGUUUCAGAUGAAACUUACUCAAUUCAUACCACCCUGAAAUGGAGGACAGAGGUGACAAACUUCAGUUUAAUAGGUUUCUCACCAAGUUGUAUGUUCCAUUGGCCCAGGAUUCUUGCACUAAUGGGUUUCUAUCACAUCAUGUCUAUAAAUGGGUGCACUUUACUGUUUGAAUUUGUAACUGAAGUACUGGAUAUUUAAGUGUGAGUAAUGUCUUCAUUAGAAAAUAGCAGAACCGCUCUUGUCUUUUAGUGUAUUUUUCAAGAAAAAAGGAAAGGAAAGACAUCAAGCAGUGGAUCACAACAUUUAUAGCACAAGAAAUAACUUGUAUAUAAGCAUCAAAAAGAUUAAGAAUUUUUUAAUAUGAAAAAUAUUUGCAGUGAUUUUAAAGUGCUUUUCCAGCAAUGUUCUUAGGGACUCCUGAGACACGGUUACUUUAUCUACUGGAUCAGUAAGGCACACAAUUAACAAUUAACAAUUAAUGUUUAUUUACAAAGUAAAGGGAAAACCUGUGUAACAUGAGAAUUUGGCAUGACAAAAUGGAGACCAUUUUGUAUCUGCUGUUGUAUCUUGUCCGGGUUGCAGACGUGCACUAUUAAAGUCCCAAGUUAAUAGAGCACAAACCCUUCUCGCUCCUCCCCCAUGUGCCCCUCUUUUUAGAUGUGUAUAACUUAAACUCGAUGGCUCAGGAAAAUUCCACUAAUUAGAAUCAUGUACAGUACCCCAGGUCGUUGUCCAGAUAUACAAGUUUGCUAAUGUAGUUAAGCCUGGAUUAUUAAACACUUUUCCUAAAUUAUUGUAAACAGAACAGCUUAGAGAAAGGUAUUCUCAGUCCUUAAUAUUGUAUAGUAGUUUAUGAGCCCCUCUCUAAAUAUUGGUAUUUUUAUAUUCCAGAGAUGUACCCAAUAGAAAAAAUUAAAAAUUAAUCAGUAUCUAAUUUAAUAUCCAUAAGUAUUUUUCCUUAGAUUUUAGUCACGUACAGUGGGCUAUGUGGAUGUCACUUGUGCUUCACCAUAGUUUACCACUAGGUGUCACUGUGGCUCUGCACUGCGCUUGUUUUGUAGCAAAGAACAGCGGCAUCCCCUCGGGAGAGAGGAGCUGCUUCCAGGGCAACAGGCAAGCGGGCUCAGAGGUUCAGGAGAAGGCAACAGAGGCCUGGAAGGGGUCUUCGUGCAUCUGUGCCAGUUGUGCAAGACGAACUCUUUGAACACUACAUGCUUUGGACUUCAGCCAGGCAGAGGCUGGAAGAAGGUUGACCAGAGCUCCCUUGCUCUGGUAGAGGGAUGGGUACAUGGAGAAGCCCCUUCUUCCCCAUGAGCCUCCCUCCUGUCAGUUCCUCUCAGCCUCCAGCUUUUAUAACUCCAGAAGCGUCACAGUUGGGUGGUUUGAUUCAGAGAGAGUUAUUUUUCUACUGCAGAAAUGCCUUGGACAAAACCAGUGCUCACUGAAUCUUUGCCACAAAAUGGAAUAGGCUAUCCCAGGGGGCAAGAGGUGCCCGCCCCUGUGCCCAGCCUCCUCUUGAUGCUCCCAGUGCCCAGCAGCCUCGCACACCCUGCCUGUCUGUUCCUGGGCUGCCCAUUUCUCAAGAAACCGACCUGCAAAGGCAGCCGGCUGCUGCCUCCACACCGAGGGCUGUGCGGUCCUGCUGCUCGCUCACUGGGAGGUGCAGCUCUUUCUCCUCUUCCUCUAGGAAUUCCAGACCGACCAUCUACCAUGACUAACAACAAUGAACAAAGGGCUUAGGGGCAAGAGCUACCUGCAAAGACGUGUCAUGGAACCCUUCACCAUGCAAUGCCUUGAACUCAGCUCUGGCUGCUCCCAAGAAAAGGUGGCUGGCUGGGGGCCUGGACACAAGCACAAUGGGGCUGGUGGAGCCACUGUGCAGAGCUACUUGAAUAAUCACUGGGUUUUCAUCAACUCCUUUUGUCAUACAGACCACUCAAGGGCUGAAGUGUUGGUAACCUUCAUUUCGGUGUCCAAAGCCUCACAGCAGGUGAGCCACCCUGAGAUGCUUGUGGCCACAUGGUGGCCACAGUCAGAGCUUUGAAAGUCAGUACCAAAUGAACGCAUAAUUGGACACCAAAAAUCAAGUGUUACUUUCAUGUUUCCUCACCCCAUCAUCUCAUUGCCUCCUGCUGACUCUGAUACCGACGCUGAGCUGACUUGCCAGGCUGCCGCUGGACGCGUAGAGAUCAGGCCAGCGCCGCGCUCAUUUUUCCAGGUAGACCUACUCUGUGGAACGGAAGUGCCCUAGCUGCUUUGUUUUUGUAGCACUUGCUGGCUGAAUUUUUCUUUUGCUAAUCGCUAACCAGAAAGUCUGGUUAGAGGGGGCUCAACUCAAUCCCUUUGGUCCCCAGCGCCAGACAAGAGUUAAUUCUGGAAAAUUCAGUACUUGAAUGUACCUGCCUUAUUGCAUACCAAUUUACUGGGGGGAAAAAAAAAGUUAAGAGAUGCCGGCUCCAGAUCUCCACUUCAUUCACAGGUGAUUUUGGAAAUCCUGUAAGUUACACUUCCUGUUCUGGUUUUGUUUUGUUUUUUGUUUCCUUUGGCUGAUUCCUGCUGAGUGAGGCCAGUUCCUCAUCAGGCUCAGGGCAGGUGCCUUUUCAGGCGUGGCCUCCUUUCCAUCUAGCACAGCAUCUUUGUCUCUGUUCUGUCUCCUCCAAAUCCAAGAUGAUUUUAAUUAGUACAGACAUGUACAGUCUACAAUUAAAGAGUGAUUUGUACUAAUAUGAUUUUGAUUCUUCCUCCUCUUUGCUGUCCUUUCAAGACACUUGCUGGAAAAAGCUUUAAUGCACUUAGUUUUCCUUUAGGUUUUCUAUGACUCAGAUGUAAAGGACUUUCUCUGUACAGUAUAUUAUCCAAUGCAUGUUUGUUCUCUCUCCUGAUAUAUUGAACACCACACAGUUGUGAAGCCGUGCAGUGGGGAUGCCCCACACCCCACAGAGGCAUCUACCCCUGUGUAUAAGGAAAGACAUUUUCCUUUGCUGUACUUGCUUGAGCAGUUUUAUUGUCUGUACAUGUGAGCUGUGUGAGAUAGAUGUGAAAAGUUCAAAUGAAUGCAUUUUCCUGCCCCAUGUAUACAGAUUGUCAUCUGUACAAGGAACUGUAUGUAUGAAAGCAAAUGUACUUAUUUAUAAAUGGCUAACACUUGGAAAA